AGAGCCUCUUGGAUCCCCACAGGGUAAUGGGUGUCCCGAUCUCGCGGGGGACUCUGUGAUCCGUGUUCCCCUGACCCUCCUAGUGCACAACUUGGCCGGGCUCACUGGGCUCCUGCACCACUGCCUGUCAGGUCCGCUGCCAGCCCCAAGCCCCCCACCAGCCAUGAGCUCCUCCAGAAAGGACCACCUCGGCGCCAGCAGCUCAGAGCCCCUCCCGGUCAUCAUUGUGGGUAACGGCCCCUCUGGUAUCUGCCUGUCCUACCUGCUCUCCGGCUACACACCCUACACGAAGCCAGAUGCCAUCCACCCACACCCCCUGCUGCAGAGGAAGCUCACCGAGGCCCCGGGGGUCUCCAUCCUGGACCAGGACCUGGACUACCUGUCCGAAGGCCUCGAAGGCCGAUCCCAAAGCCCCGUGGCCCUGCUCUUUGAUGCCCUUCUACGCCCAGACACAGACUUUGGGGGAAACAUGAAGUCGGUCCUCACCUGGAAGCACCGGAAGGAGCACGCCAUCCCCCACGUGGUUCUGGGCCGGAACCUCCCCGGGGGAGCCUGGCACUCCAUCGAAGGCUCCAUGGUGAUCCUGAGCCAAGGCCAGUGGAUGGGGCUCCCGGACCUGGAGGUCAAGGACUGGAUGCAGAAGAAGCGAAGAGGUCUUCGCAACAGCCGGGCCACUGCCGGGGACAUCGCCCACUACUACAGGGACUACGUGGUCAAGAAGGGUCUGGGGCAUAACUUUGUGUCCGGUGCUGUAGUCACAGCCGUGGAGUGGGGGACCCCCGAUCCCAGCAGCUGUGGGGCCCAGGACUCCAGCCCCCUCUUCCAGGUGAGCGGCUUCCUGACCAGGAACCAGGCCCAGCAGCCCUUCUCGCUGUGGGCCCGCAACGUGGUCCUCGCCACAGGCACGUUCGACAGCCCGGCCCGGCUGGGCAUCCCCGGGGAGGCCCUGCCCUUCAUCCACCAUGAGCUGUCUGCCCUGGAGGCCGCCACAAGGGUGGGUGCGGUGACCCCGGCCUCAGACCCUGUCCUCAUCAUUGGCGCGGGGCUGUCAGCGGCCGACGCGGUCCUCUACGCCCGCCACUACAACAUCCCGGUGAUCCAUGCCUUCCGCCGGGCCGUGGACGACCCUGGCCUGGUGUUCAACCAGCUGCCCAAGAUGCUGUACCCCGAGUACCACAAGGUGCACCAGAUGAUGCGGGAGCAGUCCAUCCUGUCGCCCAGCCCCUAUGAGGGUUACCGCAGCCUCCCCAGGCACCAGCUGCUGUGCUUCAAGGAAGACUGCCAGGCCGUGUUCCAGGACCUCGAGGGUGUCGAGAAGGUGUUUGGGGUCUCCCUGGUGCUGGUCCUCAUCGGCUCCCACCCCGACCUCUCCUUCCUGCCUGGGGCAGGGGCUGACUUUGCAGUGGAUCCUGACCAGCCGCUGAGCGCCAAGAGGAACCCCAUUGACGUGGACCCCUUCACCUACCAGAGCACCCGCCAGGAGGGCCUGUACGCCAUGGGGCCGCUGGCCGGGGACAACUUCGUGAGGUUUGUGCAGGGGGGCGCCUUGGCUGUGGCCAGCUCCCUGCUAAGGAAGGAGACCAGGAAGCCACCCUAACACUCGGCCAGACCCGCUGGCUCCCAGGCCCUGAGAGGACAGAGAUGACCACAUCCCUGCUGGAUGCAGGACCCGUCCAAAGAUGCCCCGGGGAGGGGUGUCAGCCCACGUUGCUGGCCUUUGGGGUCAAGAGGAGUAGGGAUCCCAGGCUGCCCUGGACUUAGACCAGUGUCUGAGGUGGUAACAGCGGCCGCAGGCCAGGGUUGGCCUAGACCUGGGAUUUGUGGGGAAAGCUGCUGGUGUGACCAGCUGAGCACCCAGCCAGGAGACCUGCAGCCCUGCGCCUUCCAGAAGCAGGUCCCAAAUAAAGCCAGUGCCCACCUGC